GCUUCCGGUUCUGACGGACGCUUCGGCCGUAACGAUGAUCGGAGACAUCCUGCUGUUCGGGACGUUGCUGAUGAAUGCCGGGGCGGUGCUGAACUUUAAGCUGAAAAAGAAGGACACGCAGGGCUUUGGGGAGGAGUCCAGGGAGCCCAGCACAGGUGACAACAUCCGGGAAUUCUUGCUGAGCCUCAGAUACUUUCGAAUCUUCAUCGCCCUGUGGAACAUCUUCAUGAUGUUCUGCAUGAUUGUGCUGAGAAAACUCAAGCAGAUUGCCUUUCCAUCUAGCACUGGGGCCAUAACUCUGAUACUACUGUUAACGAAUUGUGAGAUUUGCUGUAAAUGGAUUUAGGAAAAGACACGACGGGAGAAUCUGGUGUUCUUGGCCUCUGUGGGUCCAUCCCUGUAUGCUUCCCCCAGAAAGAGAGAGGACAAAAAGUUGUCUGUCCUGAGUGAUUGAGACUCCGAAUGUGGGGUUGCUGUCCAGUCUGCGUGCCACCCCAGUGGCUGUUUGCGAAGAUGCUUCCAGGACAUAGGAGAUCUGGGGAGGAUGGCAUUUCACCCUCAUCACAAGGACCGUGAUGUAUUCCCAGGAAGACUGUUGCCAAGGCUGUUCGGCUCUUGAAUCCCAGCGAUGAAACCAGGAACUCACUUUCCCGGGAUGCCGAGUCUCCAUUCCUCCAUUCCUGAUGACUUCAAGAAUGUUUUUGACCAGAAAACCGACAACCUUCCCAGAAAGUCCAAGCUCGUGGGUCUGCUUGGCCACUCAGUGCAGCUGCGAUUAACCCUAAAGGCUUUAAGGAACGGGCCACCUGUAACAGAGACACCAGCCUUCCUGUAUAGACACUAAAUUGUUAGCAAGAGUGUUGAGCUAGUUCCUGGUGAAGUGUUUCCACAGAAGACAUGUGGAGCAGUUGUGGGGAUAUUAAGGGAAACUUUCCUCUGCCUUGACCCCUUUGUUAAAUAAAAUGACUUUGGGAGCCAUUCAUUGUACAGUUGCAGGAAUGAGAGUGAUUUUAUGAUGUGGUACAUUGGGACCAUGUUCUAAAACCUUGGGUUUCUGAGUCUGCUUUUUGAGUAGGUGAUUUUGAGGUUGAAAAACCAGGGGCCUUCAUCUAGGAAAUACAGCAUUUUCCAGAAGCUUCUUUGAAAGGGAAUCCUGGUUUUGUUGCCAAAAUGAAACGCCCGGGGUUGGCGCUGAAUCCCACAACUGUGUGAUUUGCUUGUUGAGUUUUUUGUUGUCUGGUUUUUUUGUUUGUUUGUUUAUACCAAUAAGAAUGAGCCUGAAUGUUGGUGGUUUUUGAAAUCCUGACUUGGAGGUAAACCUGGAGGAAGGAAAAAAAGUAAAUAUGCAGGCUUUUAGGACUGAGUAGCCUUGAAAAUAAACCUCAUUUCUAAAAAGGA